GCCGCGCCCGUCCGCCCGCCGCUCCGCGCUCCACCCAGCGCACCCGGGCCCCGCGCCCCCAACUGCCUCCGGCGGCCGCCCAGUCCCGAGGGCGCCAUGAGGAGCCUGUGCUGCGCCCCACUCCUGCUCCUCUUGCUGCUGCCGCCGCUGCUGCUCACGCCCCGCGCUGGGGACGCCGCCGUGAUCACCGGGGCUUGUGACAAGGACUCCCAAUGUGGUGGAGGCAUGUGCUGUGCUGUCAGUAUCUGGGUCAAGAGCAUAAGGAUUUGCACACCUAUGGGCAAACUGGGAGACAGCUGCCAUCCACUGACUCGUAAAAACAAUUUUGGAAAUGGAAGGCAGGAAAGAAGAAAGAGGAAGAGAAGCAAAAGGAAAAAGGAGGUUCCAUUUUUUGGGCGGAGGAUGCAUCACACUUGCCCAUGUCUGCCAGGCUUGGCCUGUUUACGGACUUCAUUUAACCGAUUUAUUUGUUUAGCCCAAAAGUAAUCGCUCUGGAGUAGAAACCAAAUGUGAAUAGCCACAUCUUACCUGUAAAGUCUUACUUGUGAUUGUGCCAAACAAAAAAUGUGCCAGAAAGAAAUGCUCUUGCUUCCUCAACUUUCCAAGUAACAUUUUUAUCUUUGAUUUGUAAAUGAUUUUUUUUUUUUUUUAUCGAAAGAGAAUUUUACUUUUGGAUAGAAAUAUGAAGUGUAAGGCAUUAUGGAACUGGUUCUUAUUUCCCUGUUUGUGUUUUGGUUUGAUUUGGCUUUUUUCUUAAAUGUCAAAAACGUACCCAUUUUCACAAAAAUGAGGAAAAUAAGAAUUUGAUAUUUUGUUAGAAAAACUUUUUUUUUUUUUUCUCACCACCCCAAGCCCCAUUUGUGCCCUGCCACACAAAUACACCUACAGCUUUUGGUCCCUUGCCUCUUCCACCUCAAAGAAUUUCAAGGCUCUUACCUUACUUUAUUUUUGUCCAUUUCUCUUCCCUCCUCUUGCAUUUUAAAGUGGAGGGUUUGUCUCUUUGAGUUUGAUGGCAGAAUCACUGAUGGGAAUCCAGCUUUUUGCUGGCAUUUAAAUAGUGAAAAGAGUGUAUAUGUGAACUUGACACUCCAAACUCCUGUCAUGGCACGGAAGCUAGGAGUGCUGCUGGACCCUUCCUAAACCUGUCACUCAAGAGGACUUCAGCUCUGCUGUUGGGCUGGUGUGUGGACAGAAGGAAUGGAAAGCCAAAUUAAUUUAGUCCAGAUUUCUAGGUUUGGGUUUUUCUAAAAAUAAAAGAUUACAUUUACUUCUUUUACUUUUUAUAAAGUUUUUUUUCCUUAGUCUCCUACUUAGAGAUAUUCUAGAAAAUGUCACUUGAAGAGGAAGUAUUUAUUUUAAUCUGGCACAACACUAAUUACCAUUUUUAAAGCAGUAUUAAGUUGUAAUUUAAACCUUGUUUGUAACUGAAAGGUCGAUUGUAAUGGAUUGCCGUUUGUACCUGUAUCAGUAUUGCUGUGUAAAAAUUCUGUAUCAGAAUAAUAACAGUACUGUAUAUCAUUUGAUUUAUUUUAAUAUUAUAUCCUUAUUUUUGUCA